ACACGUGACGGCCCCCCUUUCCCCGCAGACGUGUGAAUGCAGCGCUGUGUCUUUAAGGGGCACGCGCGGAGGUUUUCCGUCCGGGACAAAAUGUCAGCGAGGCGCCUGGAGGGGGAUCUACCAUCUCGGACUCCCGACCCGCCGCCGGCUCCGGCCGCGUUUCCCGGGUAAAGGGCACUGCUGAUGGUUCUUCAGAACUCAGGAAUCGUGUUGCAUGCAUUGUUUCUACCCACCUGAGAUGGUUGGAAACCCUGAGGCAAUGACAGGGACCCCAGAAUCCUUGGGAAAUUACCCACUGUCUAAUUUAAAGCGUGCGGGCGCCGCAGAAUGAGGAGUGGCGAGCCGGCCUGCACCAUGGACCAGGCCCGCGGGCUGGACGACGCGGCGGCGCGGGGCGGUCAGUGUCCGGGACUGGGGCCGGCGCCGACGCCGACGCCUCCCGGCCGCCUGGGGGCGCCAUACUCCGAGGCCUGGGGCUACUUCCACCUGGCGCCGGGGCGCCCCGGGCAUCCGUCGGGCCACUGGGCCACCUGCCGUCUGUGCGGGGAGCAGGUGGGCCGCGGCCCGGGCUUCCACGCGGGGACCUCGGCGUUGUGGAGGCACCUGAGGAGCGCGCACCGGCGGGAGCUGGAGAGCAGCGGCGCCGGGAGCUCCCCACCUGCCGCGCCCUGCCCGCCGCCGCCCGGCCCCGCUGCGGCCCCCGAGGGCGACUGGGCGCGCCUGCUGGAACAGAUGGGCGCGCUGGCCGUGCGCGGCAGCCGGCGGGAGCGGGAGCUGGAGCGGCGCGAGCUGGCCGUGGAGCAGGGCGAGCGCGCCCUGGAGCGGAGGCGGAGGGCGCUGCAGGAGGAAGAGCGCGCCGCGGCCCAGGCGCGCCGGGAACUGCAGGCCGAGCGGGAGGCGCUGCAGGCGCGGCUGCGGGAUGUGAGCCGCCGUGAGGGCGCCCUGGGCUGGGCCCCCGCUGCGCCGCCGCCGCUCAAGGACGACCCCGAGGGUGACAGGGACGGCUGCGUCAUCACAAAGGUCCUCCUGUAGGGGUGUGGCCACUUCCCCACCCCAGGACAGCGCUUCUCCGUCCAAUGCCAAUGCCUUCAGACCCCGCUGGGACCGAAGCCGUAACCGAAGCCAGGCCCGCAGCCGCUACUCACUCGGAAGCUCCAGCUAACUGUAGGAUCUUCCACACCCUAAGGCUUCAGCUUGAGAAGCACUUCGAAGCCAGAGCAGAACCAAAACUCACUUCCAUGGGGUCACCGGGGGUGCCUGGGCGGCCUUUCGUGGGCAUGCACGCAAGGAAUUGGGGUGGCACACGGGACACCCGAGAGCUCCAGGAGCCCCGUGAACCCAGACCACCCAGUGCCAUGGCCACUUAGGGCUGGGAACCCGAACCUGGUGACUUUGAAAGGAUAGAGCUUCAUUCCAUACCAAAGACUUAUCACACCAUGUGCCUAUACACCCAGCAGCCCAAGGUGGAGGGUGCGUGGAAAUGAGAAAGCUUUUUACCCAAAAAAAAAAAAAAAAGAGUUCCUAAUGCAUAAUCUGCCCAACACCAAGUUCUGAAGGGUGGGUGAGGGACGUCCCCUCUAGUUUCCAUGACUGCUGUAGACCCGCAUCAUCUCUAGCCCUCAUCGGGGCAGUCCCAGAGCCCGCUUUUUUACUGCCCAUAUUAUUCAACCAAUACCAGGUGCACUCUGUCUCCCCUCGGCCAUCCUUCCCUUGCUUCAGACCUAAUGACAAGUGUGGCACAUAUGUCCACUUUCAGGCCUCACAUCUGCCACCUUAGCAAGACAUCACCUCAUCCCCUUGUCACUAGGAAGAGGGCUUCUUCCCCACAUGUCGUCAUAGUGCUCACCUCUGGGCUGAAGGGGAAAGCAUCCCUCCGCUUAAGGCCACAUCUACCUGUCAUUUUCCAUCCCAUUCCUCUCCCACGUUUACUGGGUCUUUCCUCCUGUAGUAUUCCCCCUUUCGCUGUCUCAGUCCCUCCCUUUCCCCCAGGCUCUUCUUCCUCAGCAAUGUGCAGUCUCCCUUUCUUACUGAAAAGAAAGACUUAACCCAGAAGGGCCAACAAGUCCUGGCUGCCUAUCCUUCCUCCCCAGUUUUUACUCCCUCACUCUGGGUCAGUUUUCUUUUCUUUUUUUCUUUAUGUGUGUAUAUAUUAUAUAUAUAUAUACAUAUAUACAUAUAUAUAUACAUAUAUACAUAUAUAUAUACAUAUAUACAUAUAUAUAUACAUAUAUACAUAUACAUAUAUAUAUAUAUAUAUAUAUGUAUAUAUAAUACUUUAAGUUCUAGGGUGCAUGUCAGUUUUCUAUGCUUCACCAGACUAUUUCCAAGCUGCCACAAUCUCCCAGUGACCAAAUAUGAUGAUCUAUUUGCAGCCUUCAUUUUGCUUAAUCUCUCCCUUGAAAUUGCUCUCUUGGUAGGUGGAUCCUGUUUUUCCUUCAAAGAAUUCCUUUUCCUGUUGCAUACUGGUUCCCAGUUUUUCCAUAGGCCUCUUUUUUUUCUUAUUUUUUUAUAUUGAAAAAUUCCACACAUCCAGAAAAAGUUGAAAGGCUAGCACAAUGAAUACUCAGAUACAUACUCUCCACUUGGAUUGAAUAGUUGUUAACAUUUUGCCAGAUUUACUAUUCUCUCCACCCCAUGCAUGUGUACAUAGAAUGACAUUUCGACCCCUGAGUAUUACCACAUAGAUUUCCUGAGCACAAAGACACCGUUCUACAUGAUUACAUUAAGAUGAUCAUGCCUAAAAAUAUAAACAGUAACUUCUUUAUAGCCUCUAAUACAGAGCCCUUAAUCAGUAUUCAACAAUUGUCUCCAGAAUGUUUGUCUUUAAAAACAACGACAACAACCAGGUCCCAUCAAGGUUCAUACAUUCUUUUGGUUUCAACUCUAGUCACUUUCAGUCUACAACAACCCCAACAUAUUUUCCCAUGAUACUUUUUGAAGCAUCCAGGCCAGCUGUCUUAGCAAAUGUCCUCUAUUCUGGAAGUGUCUGAUUGCUUCCUUAGGCCUAUGUCUACACUCCACUCGUGGCUCAUAUCCCUGCAGAGUUGUAAUCUCCUCUGGGCCAGGGACUCCUGAAUAUCUCCAGGCCGAGUGUUCUCCCCGGGCCUGGAGAAAACCUUCAUGCCCAAUCCCUUGCUGCAUGUCUCCACCCCUCCUUGCACAUCCUGCCUCUAUGAGUGGACGAGGCAAAUCUACUCAACCCCACAUCCCACCCCUCACCUGAUAACUAACAUUUACUGGGCACUAACAAUGUAUCAGGCACAUACUACACACUUAACAUGCAUUGCUUUCACAUACCAGCUCCAUGGUAACAUUGCGCUGGCUUUACAGCUAAAGAAACUGAGCUAGAAAGGGGUUAAGUAUCCUGUACAAGAUCACAGCUGGCCAGCAAUAGAGGUGGGAUCCCACUGCAGACAGUCUCCCCCACAGAUGCCAUGCUCCCACUGUACCACCAUGUACUGCUUCCUGAGAUCUCUGCUUCCUUCAGUCGACCCAGCUGACACCUGUUUCCUUCCUAACUCCAACUAAUUAAUUCCAGUUAAUGGAAUUGACUGGAAUUAGUGACAUUAAUAUUUACUGAGCAUUCCCCAUGUGUCAUCAGAGCUGUGCUAAAUGCUUUACAAGAAUAAUUACCUGCCAUAAAGCAACCCUAUGACAUAGGUGCUACUAUGCCCAUUUUGUAGAUGAGACAGGUUCAGGGGAGUUAGUAUCACCUUCAAGUCAUACAGUGGCUAAGAAUCUGUGGUCUCGCUGAAUGCUGGGCGCCUGCUCUGCUAAGUCUAUUUCUACAAAACAUUGCACUGCCUUCCUGUUGCCUGCCAAGCUCAGGGCCCAUUUAUCAUGCAUCUUCCCAUCCUUGUCUCCCCCAACUGUCCCUUACCUGAGUCACAAUUUCGCCAAAGCCAAAGGGAUUGUCCUAAGCCAAUGUUGAUUUAUCACUCUUCCUGCUCAAAAGCCCCCAAGAUCACCUAUCAAUCACCUACUUGAGUGCAAGCUUUGACUCUGUCACCUGACAUUCAAGUCCCCCUCUGCCCCCAUGCCAGUCUUAUCCCCUCCCCUACAUAUGCCCUAUCCUGCAGCCAAAUUGGACUCUGUUCUUCCUGACAAGACCUGGUAUUGGCAUCUCUAUGCCUCAGUUUGCCUUCCCUCCACUUUAAAAAGCCUCUUCAGUCUCGAUACAAAAAACAUCCCACACAUGUUCUAAAACCAUGCUUUCCUUGAUUUCUCCUCAUGUCAAGACAUUUCUUACUUCUCUAGUCUCCUAGCAUUUUGUGCCUCACAACCCUCAGGACAGGCCAGCUAGUGUAUGGCUGUGGGUUUUUAUCUCACCUCCCCUGCCUGACCCUGAGCCCUUGUGGGGAGUAUACUCACCCUACUCCUACAGUGCCUUGCAUUCCGUAGCUGCUCAGUACAUUAACCCAUUCAAUGUCUUUAAGAUUUUUACAAGUUAGUUUUCCUGUAAUUACUAAUCAUUUAUCUUUAAUUCUGAGUAAAAUUCACAACAACAAAUAAAAGGAAAUAGUAGUAAUUUUUUAAGCUGUUUAGUCAAUAAAGAUUUAAUGCGUCAGUUAUUGGACUGUUUGGUUUGAAGCCAAUCAACCAUUCUGGUAUGUAAAUCUACUUUUUUAUUAUACAAGUAACACAAAAUGUAUUGCCUCAGUCAAGGAAGAAGAACAGAAAAAAACAACACCCCAAAAUCCUGUCACCUCUGUAAAACUGCUAUUAAUUAACAUUUUAAUAUAUUUUCUUUUGUCUUUUGCAAUUUUUAUAUUACUCUAAGUUAUUUUCAAGUAUUGGAACUUAACUUCUUCAUAUGGAUUUAUAAAUUGGGCUAGAUGAUCUGAAUUUCCUUUUUAGAAGGAAAAAAAAAGACUUCCACAAAUGUUACUCUUCUAUCUCACCAAUUGUAAGAACCAUUAAAACAUAGGAAAGGAUUUAGAAUCUUAACUACUCCCUCAAAGAUGGCUAGUGCGAGCCUGAAUGUCCUGUUCAGGAGACAGAGAACAAUUAACCUGAGUGCUGAGUUAAGGGAAGAGGUUUUUACUUUCUGCUUUAUACACUUCUGCAUUGUUGUAAUUUUUUACACAAAGUAUGAAUUACUUUUAUGAUAAAAAAAUUUUGUUUGUAGACAACAUUCCUCUCCUUCAGCAUUCAGCAUCCUUAGUUAAAAUAAAAUCUCCAACGAAAGCAUGGAUAUAAUCCCCAUUUCCAGAAAAUCCCAGAAAGAAAUGCAGCCCUUGUUCAGUCCAACUCCAUCAUUUGAUAGAUUAGGAAAAUAGGUUCUAGAGAGUGACUUGUCCACUGUCAGGAGAUGGUGACUGUGGCGCGUCAUCUGACUCCAGCCUACUUAAUGCAUUUCAGUCUCUUUGGCCUUAAGGGCUCCUGCUGCUCACCUGAAAUCAUUCCCAAGGAACCCACAAGAGCAGGUUCCCUGGGAGGAUUCCUGAGAACACCUACACACAAGCCUCAGAGAUCUGCCAAGACAUUCUCUUUCUGAUAAAUACUAUUAAAUAUUUUUCUAUCAAAUAGUUGCCAAAUGACCUGCUCCAGUCAAAACUCAAUCUGACUUGUGACUACAAAGUAAUCUGAGGAAUCCCAAAGGUAUAUAAAAAUCUAUCCAUCUAAGUCAUCUCUCUUCAAAGUAGAAGACCUGGAAGACUAUACAGUUAUUCCCAAAAUGCUUCAACAUUUCUGGAACUCCUCUUUUAGAGUGGCCAUGAGUCCCUAGCACAUUCUUUAAAACAUCCUUGAGUUGGCAAAUACUCCUCUUUCCAGGAUAAAUUUGAUUUUUUAAAAGAACUGCCAAUUAUUCAGUCUGGUGAAUAUGGUAGAUGAUUAACCAGAUUAACAUUUCUGGUUAAUAAGGUGAGAUUAUAAUAAAACAAUGAUAAUUAUUUUAGUGUGGCUCAUAAAUUGGUCUUGAUAGUGGUAUAUUAAGGUUAAGUAAAGGCAGCAUGGUCACCAUACAGAUUAAAGCCCAUUUUAGUUGGUUUAUGAUGUGAAUGAAUUCAGGUAGCACUGGGAGUCAUUAUAUGUUUAAAUAGUAUUAAAGGUUUCUUUUUAUAAAAAUCUUAAUUAUGACAUUCUCUGAAAUCUGGUUUCACAGUAUUAAAAUGAGGCUUUAAGGAAAAACA